AAUAGCCCUUACCACCAGCAGACACACAUCAUCUGUUGUACUUGCUUAUUUGGCACAUAUGUAUCCACAGCGCCUAGAACACUGCCUGUAACGUGGAAGGUGUUCGAUCUAUAGAGUUUUGUCGAAUGAAUGAAUGAAGCCGACUAGUGCACAGGGAGUGCAGCGGCGCGAUGGUAGCUCUCUGCAGCCUCCAACACCUGGGCUCCAGUGAUCCCCGGGCUCUGCCCACCCUCCCCACUGCCACUUCCGGGCAGAGGCCAGCAAAGCGGCGGCGCAAGAGUCCCGCCAUGGCCGCUCUCACCCGGGACCCCCAGUUCCAGAAGCUGCAGCAAUGGUACCGCGAGCACCGCUCCGAGCUGAACCUGCGCCGCCUCUUCGAUGCCAACAAGGACCGCUUCAACCACUUCAGCUUGACCCUCAACACCAACCAUGGGCAUAUCCUGGUGGAUUACUCCAAGAACCUGGUGACGGAGGACGUGAUGCGGAUGCUGGUGGACUUGGCCAAGUCCAGGGGCGUGGAGGCCGCCCGGGAGCGGAUGUUCAAUGGUGAGAAGAUCAACUACACCGAGGGUCGAGCCGUGCUGCACGUGGCUCUGCGGAACCGGUCAAACACACCCAUCCUGGUAGACGGCAAGGAUGUGAUGCCAGAGGUCAACAAGGUUCUGGACAAGAUGAAGUCUUUCUGCCAGCGUGUCCGGAGCGGUGACUGGAAGGGGUACACAGGCAAGACCAUCACGGACGUCAUCAACAUUGGCAUUGGCGGCUCCGACCUGGGGCCCCUCAUGGUGACUGAAGCCCUUAAGCCAUACUCUUCAGGAGGUCCCCGCGUCUGGUAUGUCUCCAACAUUGAUGGAACUCACAUUGCCAAAACCCUGGCCCAGCUGAACCCCGAGUCCUCCCUGUUCAUCAUUGCCUCCAAGACCUUUACUACCCAGGAGACCAUCACGAAUGCAGAGACGGCGAAGGAGUGGUUUCUCCAGGCGGCCAAGGAUCCUUCUGCAGUGGCGAAGCACUUUGUUGCCCUGUCUACUAACACAACCAAAGUGAAGGAGUUUGGAAUUGACCCUCAAAACAUGUUCGAGUUCUGGGAU